GAGAAUCGCUUGAACCCGGGAGGCAGAGGGUGCAGUGAGCAGAGAUUGCACCACUGCACUCCAGCCUGGGCAAGAGCGAGACUCCCUUUCAAAACACCACGACCACCACCAACACCACCACCACCUCCACCACCACCUCCCAAUGGCUUUCCAUUGCAGGUAGAAUUUGAAUAACAACCAAACUCCUCUCCGUGGGCGGGAACCCCCUGCUGGCACCCUUGUCCACAUCUCCGCCCUCACCCCCUACCCUCACCUCCUGCCCCAAACCCCUUCUGUCUGCAUCCGCGGCACCCCAAAGUGCAUUUCUCCCUCGAGGUGGUCCUGGCUGCUGUUCUCUGUAGGAACUUUUCCUCUUGGCUCUCUUCCUGUCAUCCAUUUCAAAGUUCCCCUUUCAAGAACGUACAGAUGGAGGCAGAGUUAAAAGACCCCUCAGCCAAUCAAAAUGCACGGAUCUGAUUUGCAUCCUGAUUCAAACCGUGAAAAACCCCAAACCACAACCAACCACAGAAUCAGCCACUGAUCAUAUUUAAUGGGAUGAUUUGAAAUGUGAACAAUUAACAGAUAUUUGAUGAUAUGAAAAAAUUAUAUUUUUAGAUGUGAUCAUAGUAUUGUGAUUACAUUUUUAAAAAAAUUAGCCUCAGUGAGGUAUAAUUUACAUAAAAUAAAAUUAGCCCACUUUAAGUAUAGAAUUCAAUGUGUUUGAACAAAUGUAUGUACAGUCAUGAAACCAUAUGGUUACAUAUAAAAAAGGAGUUCUUAGGCCAGAUGCAGUGACUCGCGCCUGUAAUCCCAGCAGUUUGGGAGGCUGGGGCAGGAGGAUCCCUUGAGCCUAGGAGUUUGAGACCAGCCUGGGCAACAUAGUGAGACCCUAUCUCUACAAAAAAGUACAAAAAUUAGCCAGACGUGGUGAUGUGUGCCUGUAGUCCCAGCUACUCAGGAGGCUGAGGUGGGAGGACUGCUUGAGCCUGAGAGGUCGAGGCUGCAGAGAGCUGUGAUUACAGUACUGCACUCCAGCCUGGGUGACAGAGUGAGACUCUGUCUCAAAAACACAAGUUCUUUACCUCCAGAGAGACAUGCUGAAAUAUUUACAGGCUGUCUACCUGGUCUCCAGAAUGGACGGCCCUGUGGCAGAGCAUGCCAAGCAGGAGCCCUUUCACGUGGUCACACCUCUGUUGGAGAGCUGGGCGCUGUCCCAGGUGGCGGGCAUGCCUGUCUUCCUCAAGUGUGAGAAUGUGCAGCCCAGCGGCUCCUUCAAGAUUCGGGGCAUUGGGCAUUUCUGCCAGGAGAUGGCCAAGAAGGGAUGCAGACACCUGGUGUGCUCCUCAGGGGGUAAUGCGGGCAUCGCUGCUGCCUAUGCUGCUAGGAAGCUGGGCAUUCCUGCCACCAUCGUGCUCCCCGAGAGCACCUCCCUGCAGGUGGUGCAGAGGCUGCAGGGGGAGGGGGCCGAGGUUCAGCUGACUGGAAAGGUCUGGGACGAGGCCAAUCUGAGGGCGCAAGAGUUGGCCAAGAGGGACGGCUGGGAGAAUGUCCCCCCGUUUGACCACCCCCUAAUAUGGAAAGGCCACGCCAGCCUGGUGCAGGAGCUGAAAGCAGUGCUGAGGACCCCACCAGGUGCCCUGGUGCUGGCAGUUGGGGGUGGGGGUCUCCUGGCCGGGGUGGUGGCUGGCCUGCUGGAGGUGGGCUGGCAGCAUGUACCCAUCAUUGCCAUGGAGACCCAUGGGGCACACUGCUUCAAUGCGGCCAUCACAGCCGGCAAGCUGGUCACACUUCCAGACAUCACCAGUGUGGCCAAGAGCCUGGGUGCCAAGACGGUGGCCGCUCGGGCCCUGGAGUGCAUGCAGGUGUGCAAGAUUCACUCUGAAGUGGUGGAGGACACCGAGGCUGUGAGCGCUGUGCAGCAGCUCCUGGAUGAUGAGCGUAUGCUGGUGGAGCCUGCCUGUGGGGCAGCCUUAGCAGCCAUCUACUCAGGCCUCCUGCGGAGGCUCCAGGCCGAGGGCUGCCUGCCCCCUUCCCUGACUUCAGUUGUGGUAAUCGUGUGUGGAGGCAACAACAUCAACAGCCGAGAGCUGCAGGCUUUGAAAACCCACCUGGGCCAGGUCUGAGGGGUCCCAUCCUGGCCCCAAAGACCCCUGAGAGGCCCAUGGACAGUCCUGUGUCUGGAUGAGGAGGACUCAGUGCUGGCAGAUGGCAGUGGAAGCUGCCCUGUGCAACUGUGCUGGCUGCCUCCUGAAGGAAGCCCUCCUGGACUGCUUCUUUUGGCUCUCCGACAACUCCGGCCAAUAAACACUUUCUGAAUUGA